GUAAACAAACGGAGCUGCGGAGGAGCGGGUCCCGGGAUGUGACCGGGGCUCUGCUUGUGGCUGCGGCGGUGGCUUCUGAGGCUGUCGGGUCUUUGCGGGUUGCGGAAGGGGGCCCCAAUACCCUUCUUCUUCAGGUCUUAAGAAGCUGGCCGUGGUGCAAUAAGGAACUUAAAACAAUGGAAGAGCGGAAAGUGAAGAGGAGGAGUCCUAAGUCUUUUAGUGCCCACUGUACUCAGGUUGUCAAUGCCAAAAAAAAUGCCAUUCCAGUGAGUAAAAGCACAGGGUUUUCAAAUCCUGCAUCACAGUCAACUUCACAGCGACCAAAGUUAAAAAGAGUGAUGAAAGAAAAGACCAAACCUCAGGGUGGAGAGGGCAAAGGCGCUCAGUCAACUCCGAUCCAGCACUCCUUCCUCACUGAUGUCUCAGAUGUUCAGGAGAUGGAGAGAGGGCUGCUCAGUCUUUUGAAUGAUUUCCACUCUGGAAAACUUCAAGCAUUUGGUUAGGCAUUUUCCAGGAUAUGCUUAGGACUGUGUCUUUUCUCAUCAAUCUGCCUGGGAAUCAGUGAGCCCUUCAUAUCUGCUGACUCAUCUUUCAUCUCACGUAACAUAUUUUCUAUUGUUUAUUAUUUUUCUUCCAUCUCUUCCUUUUUAGCCUCUGAAGCUUCUAUUGUUCUCAUGGUAGGUCACCUAGAUCCGUCCUCUGACUCUCAUCUUUUCCCAUAUGAUUUCUACCUCUUUAUAUUUUUACUGUACAUUUACAUACAUAAACACAAACAUACAUACAUACACACAAACACGUAUCUUGAGAUAUUUCUGUUUCUUCCACUUGACCUUCCAGGUUACUAAUGUUGAAAAACAUGACUAAAAUAGAGGAAAUAUGACAUAUUUUACUGUGAAGAAAGGACGAUUUUGAGAGAGCCAUAACUAGCUUCAACAUUAGUAGUCCUUAACAUAAUGUCGUAUAGUCCAUUUAUGAAGAUGUUAUAAAGCUGGCUAGAGGAAACUAGCAUAAUUUACAUUAAUUCAUAUUUAUUUAGGAUAUGUACUUCAACUUUAGCUGAGGUAUAUUUUACCUGUAUAGUACCUUUAGGAAAAACAGAAAGGUUUUUUUUUUAAAAAAUUCUACUAUCAAGGGAUUGCAGAGUCUGUACUUAAACUGAAUGAAAAGAUAAUACGUUAUGUGUAUAAAUUAGUUGCUCUGGGCAGAUAAUGUCACUUCAGAGGACUCUUGGUCAAUAUGUAAUGUAAGACCUAUUCUUUAGCAAUUAAGUUGUCUUGACAACUGUGUGUACAAUUAAAAAUAUUACAUAGUGUU